GGUUCUGGGAGCCCUGAAGACCUGGCGGAGCCCAGCGCGGAUGGAGGCCUGAGGGUGGCGGGGGCGGAGCGCGCCGCGAGCUGGGGGCAUGUCCGCGGCGGGCGCCGUCUAGAGGAAGGCCAAGCAGCCGCCACCACGCUGUCGGUCGCGGAGAGACGCAAGCGAGCCAGGCCGAGGGCCGCGGCGGCGAUGCAGCGACGGCGUCGCCCUCCGCCGCCCACCUCCCGGCUGCCCGAGGGCUGCGGGGGAGGAGGCGGUGGCAGCGAGGAGGUGGAAGUGCAGUUUUCCGCCGGGCGUUGGGGCUCGGCCGCGGCGGUUUCGGCGGCAGCGGCGGCGGCCACGCGCAGCACCGAGGAGGAGGAGGAGAGGCUUGAGCGUGAGCACUUCUGGAAGAUCAUUAAUGCCUUCCGCUACUACGGCACCAGUAUGCAUGAGCGGGUGAACCGAACAGAAAGACAGUUUCGAUCACUUCCAGCUAACCAACAGAAACUACUUCCUCAGUUUCUUCUUCACUUGGACAAGAUCCGGAAAUGCAUUGAUCAUAAUCAAGAAAUACUACUGACCAUUGUGAAUGAUUGCAUACAUAUGUUUGAAAAUAAAGAAUAUGGAGAAGAUGGGAAUGGAAAGAUUAUGCCAGCAUCUACAUUUGACAUGGAUAAGUUAAAAUCCACGCUGAAACAGUUUGUGAGAGACUGGAGUGAAACUGGGAAAGCAGAAAGGGAUGCCUGUUACCAGCCAAUCAUUAAAGAAAUUUUAAAAAAUUUUCCAAAAGAGAGAUGGUAAAUUUCUAGGACUCUGUUUAUGCCACAGUAAGUACAUGGGGAAUUUAAUGUCUUUAUACUCAGGCUGGAGUUAACACAAAUUUAUGUCAGCUAGCCUUUUAUUGUGUGUGUGUGUGUGUGUGUGUGUGUGUGUGUGUGUGUGUGUGUGUUUUAAUUUCACUGAAGGCCUUUUCUAAUUGAACUGCCUAUAGAAGAUCAUAUACUUGCCGGGCUCGGUGGCUCACGCCUGUAAUCCCAGCACUUUGGGAGGCGGAGGUGGGUGGAUCACGAGAUCAGGAGAUCGAGAUCAUCCUGGCUAACACGGUGAAACCCUGUCUCUACUAAAAAUACAAAAAAAUUAGCCGGGCGUGGUGACAGGUGCCUGUAGUCCCAGCUACUCAGGAGGCUGAGGCAGGAGAAUGGUGUGAACCCGGGAGGCGGAGCUUGCAGUGAGCCGAGAUUGCGCCACUGCACUCCAGCCUGGGUGACAGCGAGACUCCGUCUCAAAAAAAAAAAAAAAAAGAUCAUAUACUUAAUGAAAUAUGUGUAAAAUUAACUAUAUUUGUGGUCAUUAAAAUAUUUUUCCUAAGGAAACACAUAUAUCAGUUUCUCCAAUCUGUCUAUGUUUCAAGUUUUUAAUAUGCCUGAGUUUGCAAGCACAAGCAGCUUUGAAGCCACAGAUCGACUUGCUUUUGUAUAGAGUCUGUUUGUUAAUUAAGGAAAUGCUGUUUUCGUAUCCUCUGGUUUUUGUUUUAAAUAGUAUUUGAACACUACUCUAGUGAGCAGUUGCUCAUUGAAAUUUAUGAUAUAUAUGUUUUUAAUUUAAAGAAUGAGCUUAGGGUUUAAACCUUUUUCUCACGUAUGAACAUAAACAUAAUGUAAUAACUCUUCUUAAUUGAUGGUCAGACCUGUAUGUAUUGAAAUUUAAAAAAAAAUUUUUCCAAGUGAAUGUCUAAUAAUUUAAAUAUAAGAAUUCAGUGCUGUAAAGCUUAUAGUAGGUAAGGAAAUAUAGAUUCUUAAGUUUGCAUCCUAUCUGGAAGGAAGGCUAACAUGUAAAAUCACAUUUUUUGAGUCUAAAAGUUGCUGGACUAUAUUUUUUAGAUCUUAAUUUCAUUAGCCCAUUCAAUUUUAGAAGACUUUGAAGUGAUUUGUGGGGGAAAAUCUGUUAUGUCUUUGCAUUUUAAUAUAUAUACACAAACACUCCAAAAAGAUACUGAUGCACUACUGACUGGUUGAAUUCGUUUUUUCUUUUAUAUAGUUGGGCAUUAGGAAAAAAAUACUCUGAGCUUUAACGAAGCAUUUUUUUUCCACUUAAGAUAAAAUAAAUAAUGUAAAUUAUAGUUCAUGAAAAGAUUCUUUUAGCUAGGAGAACUCAUUUUUAAAAAGAAAAUGGAGGAAAUUGGAGAAAAUGUAGACUGCCAAAUAGUGCAGGUGGUAGUUCAGAGACUAAAGAUAGAUUUCUCCCUCAUCCUGAGACCAAAGACAGGUAUGUGUUUCAUAUUUCUUUCAAGUCAAGAUUUCAAGUGCUUACAGAUCUAGAAGAAUAACACAGUAGAAAAACCACUCAGCAUUCAUAACCCAGUAGACAAAUCCUGUAAAUAGAUCACAGAAAAAGAAAUACAGGACACUCAAUCUCAUAGGGAAAUGCAAAUGUAAAAACCACGUUAAGAUGCCAUUUUUUACUUAUUUUAUUGCAAAGAUUUAAAAGAUAACUAUUAGUGCAGGUGUGAGGAAACAUAAAUAUGUUGCUGGUGGAAGAAUAAAUUAGCAAAAAAUUAUGUAGAACAAUGUGGCUUAUUUGUCAAAAUUCAAAUGCAUAUCUUGGCCAGGCGCCGUGGCUCACGCCUGUAAUCCCAACACUUUGGGAGGCUGAAGUAGGUGGAUCACCUGAGGUCAGGAGUUCAAGACCAGCCUUGCUAACAUGGUGAAACCUGUCUCUACUAAAAAUACAAAAAUUAGCUGGGUGUGGUGGCACGGGCCUGUAGUCCCAGCAAUUUGGGAGGCUGAGGCAGGAGAAUUGCUUUAACCCUGGAGGCGGAGGUUGCAGUGAGUCAAGAUUGUGCCACUGCACUCUAGCCUGGGCGACAGAGCGAGACUCCGUCUCAUAGCAAAACAGAACAAAACAAAACAAAAAACAAAUGCAUAUCUUGAUUCUUGAAGUUCAAUUUAAGGGAAGCUGUUCUACAUAUAUAUUUCUGCAUGUGAAAGUUAUUUAUGCCACUACAUUAGUGUAGUGUGGGAAGUAAAAUUUUUCAAAAUAAAAAGUUAUUCAUGCUAAGGGUAUUCGUUUUAACAUUAUGAUAGUGAAAGAUUGGAAACAAUAUAAAUAUCCUUAAUUAGGAGAUUUUGAUAAAUUAUGUUACAGUCAUGCAGUGAGUUAAGGAAGCUCUGUGUACUGCUGUGAAGGAGAUUCAGGGGUAUUGUAUUAGAUCAGGGGUUGGCAAAUGUUUUCUUGAAGUGCCAAACAGUAAAUGUGUUAGGCUUUGCCGGCAAUGUCGUCUCUGUUGAGACUGCUUAGCGCCUUGUUGCAGGAAUGCAGCCAUAAACAAUUCUUAGAUGAGUGAGUAUGGCUGCGUUUUAGUAAAACUUCAUUUACAAUGACAGGUGACUGGCCUGCAAGCCAUAGUUGCUGUACCUGUGUUAAGUGAAUGACGCGAAGUGAAGAACCUUGGUAUGUAAACUAUAAUAGAACUGUGAAUGAAUUAUUGAAAGCAUAGAGAAGAGAGUUCAGGGAACUUUGCCUGGGAUAUUUAGGAAAUAUAGAUGAAGUGAUAAUUUAUAAUAAUAAGGUAAUUGAGUUUCUGUGGGUAAGAGCUCUAAAGAAAGUCUUCUGGGAUCAGUGAGAAGUUGUCUGGCUGAAAUAAAGAGUUCUUUGUUGGGAGUUGAUGAAGAGGUAAGUUAGGAGAUGCUAAACACUCCUGAUUUAUAGUCAAUUUUCUAUGAUGAAUAAAAAAAUUUUUGGCUGGGUGUGGUGGCUCAUGCCUGUAAUCCCAGCACUUUGGGAGGCCAAGGUGGGUAGGUUACUUGAGCCCAGGAGUUCAAGACCAGCCUGGGCAACACGGCGAAACCCCAUCUCUAAAAAUAAAAAAAUUAGCUGAGCAUGGUGGCACACACCUGUAGUCCCAGCCACUUGGGAGGCUGAGGCAGGAGGAUCGUCUGAGCCUGAGAGGCAGAGGUUGCAGUGACCUGAGAUGGCACUAUUGCACUCCAGCCUGGGCAACAGAGCAAGACUGUCUCAAAUUUAAAAAAAAGAAAUUCAAUACUAGCUCUGUUAAACCUUGACAUUUUGCCAUAUUUGCUUUAGAUCUCUUUUUCAUAUUAAAAAAAAAUUUUUUUUGACUGCCUCUGCAGAGCAGGGCUAUGCCACAGGCAGUGUGCUCAGGGCAGCCAUAUUUUUUAAAAGAAGCAAUUUUAUUUUUAUUUUGAAAAUUUCAAUGUAAUAAAAGAUUAUUAAUGAGAUGUUUUUCAUUCCUUUUUGUACUGUCUUUAAAUUUGGUGUUCAUUUUACACUUACAGCACGUCUCAAUUUGCAAUAGCCACAUUUUAAGUGUUCAGUAGCCACAUGUAGUUAGUGGCUUUUACUGUACUGUACUAUGAUUCAAAGAGAACCACUGUAGGUACUUAAAAGUUGUAUUUACUUCUACCACUAGGGGUCAGCCAAGUGUCAUAAUGACCCAACAAGACAGCAUUUUGUGUUGGAGUUUUAAAAUUUACAACUGCAGUGCAAAGAUCGUUCUGUGUGUAACAAAGGAAACCUCUGUCAAGAGUAAUGUUUACUGCUGGUGAAAAAGCUGGAGCAGAAAGGUUGAUGGAAGUGUGAUCUAUGGCCUCUUUAGACACAUGGACUCUGUCCUUACAGAUGUAUCCCUUCUCCGUUCCUGUUUGUCUUGAAUAAACUGUUGAAACUUUUCCUCCUGUUAUUAGGGAGGUCACAUUGUAGUAAAUGUACUACUGCUUCUCCACAUUUGGGCCUUAUUAACUAGGUAAACUUGUUGGCUUGCUUGUUUUCACUAAGAAUCUCAAGUAGGCACCAUUUGAUUACUGAGCCACAUAUUGUAUGCCUUUCUAUUCUGGCUUUAAAAAAAAAAUUCAGCCUGGUUUAAGGUUGUCUCACCAUUAAGGUCUGUAUUAGAUUUGUGUUUCUUUUUCUCCACAGAAAUGACCUCAUAGAAAUGCCCUAGACUUCAUACGGAUUCAUAGCAGAAAUUCCCACUUAGAGUGCGUUAGUUUCAUGCACAUCACAGUUAGAGGAACUUUUCAUUAUGCUGUUAAUAUCCCUUGUGUAAAGACCAAAUGAAGAAAAUCUAGCUAAGAACAAAGAUUUAGGGAAAAAUUUUCUCCAUCUUACCCAUUCAUUGCAUAGUUCCUGAUCAUUUUUUCAGUUCUAGAGGGUUUGUUUUAAUGCAUUUCUUACAUGUCCACUUCCUCUUUGUCAUAAUGCCAGUAAUUUACAUCUAUAUUAGUGUCUGUUAACUCUUAAGAUAGGACUUUGAUAUAUUCUUCAUUCUGUGACUUGAUGGGUAGCCUUUCAAUAGCAGUUUUAAUACAAGGUACUGUUAAUAUAUUUUCUGCCAUUAGGUUGAGGUGGAGAGUUCUAUGGUUCUGUUUAGUUAAGGAGAAUUUGAUAAAAGCAGUCAUUAAGUUAACUUUCUGUAAGUUAGCAAAAUAAUUGUUGUUAACAUUAUGUCACAGCUUUCCCUUCAGGGUAGCAUAAUUUCUAACUCCUGCAUGGUAAUAUUUUACUGGGGUCAUCAGCCAUUUGGAAAUUGAUUGCUGGUUAUUUUUAUAUAAAGAUUUAAAUACUAUAUGAAUUUACUUCCAAAUCCUUUUGCUUUCUGUUGCAUGAGUUUGAUCAGAUAAUUAAAAAAAAAAUUCUAAACUGAGAACAGCCACUUGCUGGGGUAAGGGUAGAAAUGCAUGUUAUGAUUGGACAGAUGGGAACUGAGAAAAGAAAGGUAAUUCUCCAGAGUAGGGGUUUCGGUGGGUCUGGUAGGGAGUGAGAAAUGAGAGAGCGUUAGGUCUGAGUAGGAUGCCAUCAUGGCAGUUCCCUUAUAUAAGGAAUAGCACAGAGUCCUAGAGCUAUGAGUUUUCAAAAGCCCCAUAGUGUUCUUUCUUAUUUUGAAGUGGGACAUGCAAAGGUUAUAUGGGCUACUAGUAAAGUGCCCUGUUGCUGCUUGGAGCAUGCCAAACUUAAAGGCCACAUAGUUAAAGAUAAAAAAAUCAUUAGUAGGAGUAGAUUUGGAAAUUGGAUUUGAUUUGUGAACCAAAUUUAGGAAAUACAGUAGUGAAGUUUCUUUUUACUUCCUGACAUGAUAUUAGCUGAUUGUAUACAUUUUCCUUUGGCUUCUUAUAAGACUACAAUUUUAGUUUCCUCGGGAUUAUAUUGAUUUGCCAAAAUUCCUGAGAAAAAGCCUUGUUUUGGUAAAACUUUUAGUGGUUUGAAAGUGGAAUGAUGGAUCUUACGUGAAGGAAAUAUGUAAUGGCAGUGUGGUGCUAGUAGGUAGAGAUCAGUUUGGUUGUGAACCUCUGGUUUGGUGUAAUAUAUUUGUUAUCAUGUAUGUUUAAUUAGAGGGCCGUUUCCCAUUUUCCCCAUGAAAAUAUCCCCUCCCCCAAAUUCUUCUGUCAACUAAAAUAUAUAGGGAUUUAGAGAUAUACCUGACACAUUAAACUCUACAUCUGUUUAAUCUAACAUAAACAAUUGAGUUACAUAUAAAAUUUAGAAAUAAAGUUAUGUUGUAUUUAUUGUCCCAUAUGAUGAAGUACUUUUGUUCAAACUCUUCAUAUUUAAUUGGGAUCCCUUUGGAAUAAUUUGUCUUUCUAAGAUAGUUGUUCAGGGUGACAGCUAUUAGGAAUAUGAGUGACUUUAUAAGUCUUGAGAUGUAAGGGGACUCCUUUUUUCUGAAAAAUAAUUUUUGAGGGGUAAAACCCUCAUCUGAUAUCGGAACAUACAUAAUAAUUCCUUAUACCUUUUAUUUUUGAUAUUUAGAAGUAUUUCUUGAUUGUGAGAAGUCAGAGUCUUAGCUUAUUCUUAUUGAGUAAAUGAGUAAGUUUUUAGUUGUUAAUGUGGAUUUUGUCUUUUCCUUUUUUUCUUUGAGGGGUUGGACAUAAUUGCCUUAUUUCA